AGGCGCCGGGCCGAGCCGAGCGCCGAGCAGGGAGCGGGCGGCCGCGCUCCGGGCCGGGGUCCCGGGGGAGCAGAUCCUCAGAAUGGCCCUUGGUGCUGCAGGCGCGGUGGGCUCCGGGCCCAGGCACCGAGGGGGCACUGGAUGACUCUCCAGGUGCAGGACCCUGCCAUCUAUGACUCCAGGUCUUCAGCACCCACCCACCGUGGUACAGCGCCCCGGGAUGCCGUCUGGAGCCCGGAUGCCCCACCAGGGGGCGCCCAUGGGCCCCCCGGGCUCCCCGUACAUGGGCAGCCCCGCCGUGCGACCCGGCCUGGCCCCCGCGGGCAUGGAGCCCGCCCGCAAGCGAGCAGCGCCCCCGCCCGGGCAGAGCCAGGCACAGAGCCAGGGCCAGCCGGUGCCCACCGCCCCCGCGCGGAGCCGCAGUGCCAAGAGGAGGAAGAUGGCUGACAAAAUCCUCCCUCAAAGGAUUCGGGAGCUGGUCCCCGAGUCCCAGGCUUACAUGGACCUCUUGGCAUUUGAGAGGAAACUGGAUCAAACCAUCAUGCGGAAGCGGGUGGACAUCCAGGAGGCUCUGAAGAGGCCCAUGAAGCAAAAGCGGAAGCUGCGACUCUAUAUCUCCAACACUUUUAACCCUGCGAAGCCUGAUGCUGAGGAUUCCGACGGCAGCAUUGCCUCCUGGGAGCUACGGGUGGAGGGGAAGCUCCUGGAUGAUCCCAGCAAACAGAAGCGGAAGUUCUCUUCUUUCUUCAAGAGUUUGGUCAUCGAGCUGGACAAAGAUCUUUAUGGCCCUGACAACCACCUCGUUGAGUGGCAUCGGACACCCACGACCCAGGAGACGGACGGCUUCCAGGUGAAACGGCCUGGGGACCUGAGUGUGCGCUGCACGCUGCUCCUCAUGCUGGACUACCAGCCUCCCCAGUUCAAACUGGAUCCCCGCCUAGCCCGGCUGCUGGGGCUGCACACACAGAGCCGCUCAGCCAUUGUCCAGGCCCUGUGGCAGUAUGUGAAGACCAACAGGCUGCAGGACUCCCAUGACAAGGAAUACAUCAAUGGGGACAAGUAUUUCCAGCAGAUUUUUGAUUGUCCCCGGCUGAAGUUUUCUGAGAUUCCCCAGCGCCUCACAGCCCUGCUAUUGCCCCCUGACCCAAUUGUCAUCAACCAUGUCAUCAGCGUGGACCCUUCAGACCAGAAGAAGACGGCGUGCUAUGACAUUGACGUGGAGGUGGAGGAGCCAUUAAAGGGGCAGAUGAGCAGCUUCCUCCUAUCCACGGCCAACCAGCAGGAGAUCAGUGCUCUGGACAGUAAGAUCCAUGAGACGAUUGAGUCCAUAAACCAGCUCAAGAUCCAGAGGGACUUCAUGCUAAGCUUCUCCAGAGACCCCAAAGGCUAUGUCCAAGACCUGCUCCGCUCCCAGAGCCGGGACCUCAAGGUGAUGACAGAUGUAGCCGGCAACCCUGAAGAGGAGCGCCGGGCUGAGUUCUACCACCAGCCCUGGUCCCAGGAGGCCGUCAGUCGCUACUUCUACUGCAAGAUCCAGCAGCGCAGGCAGGAGCUGGAGCAGUCGCUGGUUGUGCGCAACACCUAGGAGCCCAAAAAUAAGCAGCACGACGGAACUUUCAGCCGUGUCCCGGGCCCCAGCAUUUUGCCCCGGGCUCCAGCAUCACUCCUCUGCCACCUUGGGGUGUGGGGCUGGAUUAAAAGUCAUUCAUCUGACAGCAGCCGUGUGGUCAUUGGAAACUGGGGAGGGGAGGGGGAGAGAAGGGGAAGGGAAGAAGGUGGGGAGGCAGUGGGUCCCUCGGGACGACUCCCCAUUCCCUUCCCUUGGAUUCUUCUCCUUACUCAAUUUUCCCUAGACCUAAAAACAGUUUGGCAGAAGACAUGUUUAAUAACAUUUUCAUAUUUAAAAAA